CAGGUACAGAGUGAGCAGUAUAGGGCUGUGGCUGAGAGCCUGUGGUCUCAGUGGUGAGGCCACAAGCUGAGAGGUUGGUAGGGUGACCAGUUGUUGUCAGGUGUGUAAGCCUCUCUUGGUUUCCUGGUCAUAGACAGACCUACUCUGGCUGGAGAAUGACCCCUCAGCCAGCCACACUGGCCAGCCACCUCACAGAGAUACUCAAAGACCUCAAAGACACACACCACGUAUGUGGAUGGCCACCUUGGGGAGGGUAAGAAGCUAAGAAACUGAGCCCCUGCCACCACUAGUGGCCUCUUGUUUGCCAUAACACUCCAGAGCACCGGAAACUCAUCUUGGUUGUAGAGCCACCUGGGGCAGGGGUAGAUAACAGCCCAAGGAGUCCAGAAACUUUCUCUUCUCCUCCUAGUGAAGAGCCUCCCUCAGCCUAACGCUGGUGGCUCUUUCGGCAAGACUAAAAGCCAUGCUGGUCACAGGCUCAGGGCACCCCCUCCAGGUGAAUAUGGUAAGAAUCCAAGAACAGGGUGGGGCACAGACGCAUGCGGGAAAGAGGUGAGGGGCAGGCAGUUGUUGGCUCUGCCUAGAACUGCUGCCCCAACAUGGACUCCAUACCCCAUCAAGAGGCUGGCCCAAGGCCUGGGCAGAACCUAAGUGCCCAUGAGUACCCUCUAUUAGGAUGGCAUCCCUGGUGGGGCAGACCCAGGGAGGUGGCAUUGCCUCCUUCAAGCCAAUCACAGACAAAACACUGAGCCUCCCACAACCUGUACAGCCUCACAGCAGGCUGGGUGAGAAUGGUUCACACCCCCAGCCCUGAGUUUCCUACUGUAUUCACUGCCAGGCCAGGGGCUGAACCACCUUCUCACCCUUAGGGAAAAUGCAACUCACUGGGCACAUGCCUCCUGCAAGUUUGCACUUCAGACUCCCCUUUCAUCAGAAACCAUCCCCUGCACCCAUUCUCACUACUCCCUGCCACAGGCCACGUCCUCUUGAGUUCUUGGUAAGGCAUCCCCCGAUGUGGCUUUACAUUGGGGUGAACCUGGUGAGUUCUCAGAAAUGUCUGCACAGCAAGAUGAGCACCUGGCCUCCCAAUCGCAGCAUCUCCCCUCACCCCACCCCUUGCAGUAGAGCUGCUCUCUUGGCCCAGACCCAUCCAAGAAUCAGGGGGCCACAUGGGAGCCAAAGUCCACACUUGAUACUCAGAACCCUGGCACAUAUGGCUGGUGCCAGGUCAGCUCUGAAGGAACUCAAAAGUCACCAUGCCCUGACCCUGGGAAGCCGGAGACAGCAAAUGAUCUCUUCGCCAGAGAUCACGUGUUUUCAGGAGCCACAGGUUUUGUACAUCAGGAAGAAGAAGAGGCUGGAGAAGCUACGCCACCAGCUCAUGCCCAUGUACAACUUCGACCCCACGGAGGAACAAGAUGAGUUGGAGCAGGAGCUGCUGGAGCAUGGGCGGGACGCCGCCUCUGUACAGGCUGCUACUUCUGUGCAGGCCAUGCAGGGCAAGACUACUCUGCCCUCCCAGGGCCCACUGCAGAGACCCAGCCGGCUGGUGUUUACCGAUGUGGCCAAUGCCAUCCAUGCGUGAGUGGCCUGGGACAAGCCUGGACUUCUGAUAGAGACCCAUCACGGUGCCUACAGAGCUCCCCACUCCCUGAUUGUCAAGACCUACUCUGAAGAUCUUCCCUGCCAAGACACAAGAGGGCUGAGCCAGGUCCUAGCUGUUCUCCAGACCCACCUGCUGACUUUAGACUCUAAGAGAGGGCCCUAGCCAGGCUGGACUUCUGACCACUGACUUCUCCUGACCUGAGGGCCCUGGCACAGAGGGCAUCCCUCAUGCUGAGAAGGUCAAGAGCCUCUGCUGGCUUCCUCAUCCCCUGUCCAGAUCCCUCACAUCAGGGUCUGCCCCGCUAAUGUGGAGGAAAUGAGGGAGAUACGGAGUGGGAGGGAUUGGGGGAGGAAAGGGGAGGUUUCCCUCUGUUAGGGAGAGACCUGUUUUUUGGAAUCUGGAGCCUCCUCUGGGGUGGGGAGAGGAAACCACCCAAGUUAUAGGGACAGGGUAGGGCAGCAUCUGUUAUGGGCCCUGAGAAGCCCAGAGAUGGAGCUGAAACUGUCCAGUAUGCAAGGAUGCCAGGAGAAGGGCAAUUCACACCCAGGGUCCAUCCAUACUACGGAGGGUCCAGGAGGUCUCCCAGCCACCCAUCCUUGGCAACCAGAUGUUACUGGGGCCAAGCUAGGAUGGGAGCUGAGGGGGAAGGAAGUAGGGGAAUGGAAGUGGAAGGAUGCAGCCCCCCCAGACCUGCCGAGAGGCCUCAUGCAUGUGCAUGAGUGUGCCCAUGGGCAGACAUGUGCCUGUCCCAGCACAGCGGGCAGAAUGAGAUUGUCCACACUGGCCCCACCCUCCAAGUCGACCUCUACCCCAUGGUAUGUAGUGGAGCAUCAGGGUAGGCUAUCUUCUCUGCCUUCAAUCUUCAGGGACUGCAGGGAAGAGGGAAGCACGCACAGCACGGUUCCUCUCUCCACUGCAUUGUUUCACUGGGCUCACCUGCUUCUGAAAACGGCUCCCUGUCUUGGGCUCUAAUGAGGAUCUGGGGUUGGGAGAGGCUGUUGGUCUGAGGGCAGUAAUCACAGGCUGCAGGCUAGAGGGGGCAGUUAUGACUGCCUGAAAGUGGGUGAGGGAUUGCACUUCAGAAAAACAUCUAAAAAACUUAGUCUAUGUUUGAAUUCCCCACCUCCAUCCCAUCUAUGGGAAGAGCCGUUCAGUGUUUAGAGAGUGGGGAGAUGGGUCCCUGCACUUGGCCUCUCCAUAAGCCUUGGAGGGUCAGGGCUGAUACCAGGGGUCCUGGCAAGCCAUUGGGCAGAGACAGACCACAAGAGCAGGGCAUUUUUUUACGCUGGGCAUACAUAUGCACACAAGCAUGCACAGAGGCAUGUCCCGUGCCCAGCCUCUCCACCGUCACUGUCCGCUGCUGGCUGGAGGGGAUGCAGGGGUAGUGUAUGCAGACCUUCCACUGGGCAAAUGCCAUGUGUCAGGAGGGAAAGGCCUAGGAAGCCCCCAUGGGGAAGGUUCUGGAUUUAUUCCCUCCUCUAAAUGCUAUAAAUACGUUAGCACUUGAGUCGACUGGAGGCUGCCAGGAAUUCAGGAUGCAUACAGCUGUAAUUUAACCCAGAGCAGCUCCACGUGAGAGCAUUAAAGAUGUAAUGAAGAUGUUUACAUGGA